CAGGGAGAAAGGCUGGUCCCCUAGUCUUGUUAUCUCAAAUGAGCUCAAUAUCUGUCUAUAUCUAUCUUCGACUGAAAAGUGUGUUGAAGUUGAGUGCCGACAUGUAAGACAUUCAAUUUAAAGCUUUGUUACUUGAAAUCAUUUGAACUCCUCUUGAGCUGUCCCCUCAUCUGGCUCUUGUCUUAGCCGUUGCAGGUGAACCACUGGAUGGAUGGCUGAAAGGAAUUACACCGUAGUGACGGAGUUCUUCCUUACUGCAUUUACUGAACAUCUCCAGUGGAGGGUUCCUCUCUUCCUCAUAUUUUUGAGUUUCUAUCUUGCCACUAUGUUAGGGAACACAGGCAUGAUCCUCCUGAUCCGUGGCGAUCGUCGGCUCCACACCCCGAUGUACUUCUUCCUCAGCCACCUUUCCUUGGUGGACAUCUGCUACUCGUCCGCCAUCAUCCCUCAGAUGCUGGCUGUGCUGUGGGAGCACGGCACAACCAUCUCCCAGGCUCGCUGUGCAGCUCAGUUCUUCCUCUUCACCUUCUUUGCCUCCAUCGACUGCUACCUUCUGGCCAUCAUGGCCUAUGACCGCUACACGGCCGUGUGCCAGCCCCUGCUUUAUGUCACCAUCAUAACCGAGAAGGCCCGCUGGGGCCUAGUCACUGGGGCUUACGUUGCUGGUUUUUUCAGUGCCUUUGUUCGAACGGUCACAGCCUUCACUCUCUCCUUUUGUGGAAACAAUGAGAUCAACUUCAUUUUCUGUGACCUCCCUCCUCUAUUAAAACUCUCCUGUGGGGACAGCUACACUCAGGAAGUGGUGAUUAUUGUGUUUGCUCUUUUCGUCAUGCCUGCCUGUAUCUUGGUGAUCUUGGUAUCCUACCUGUUUAUCAUUGUGGCCAUCCUGCAGAUCCACUCUGCUGGAGGCCGGGCCAAGACCUUCUCCACCUGCGCCUCCCACCUCACUGCCGUCGCUCUUUUCUUUGGCACCCUCAUCUUCAUGUACCUGCGAGACAACACAGGCCAGUCCUCCGAGGGAGACCGAGUGGUGUCUGUGCUCUACACGGUGGUGACCCCAAUGCUGAAUCCCCUUAUCUAUAGCCUGAGAAACAAGGAGGUAAAAGAGGCCACUAGGAAAGCCCUGAGCAAAUCAAAGCCUGCUAGAAGACCCUAAAUGGACCCUUGUGAAAUAUAUCAUUCCUUAGUUUCCCCAUCUUUUCUGUCUUUUCUCAAUAGCACCUUCUGGAGAGACUUUCCUAAAUAACCCUAUGCAAAAUCGCACCUGAACUUCCCACCUCCACUUUCUGAUUUAUUAUUCCAUGUAAUACUUAUCAUCAUCUGACAUAUUAGAUGUUAUAUGUGUUUGACAUUUUCUAAUGCUCACAACUAGAAAGUAAGCAACAUGAGAGCAAAUACUUUUUUAUCUGAGCUUCAUUUCUAUAUGUCCAGUUCCUAGCAAAGCACCUAGCAUGUGAAAGGCACUCAAUAAAUAUUUGUUGAGUGAAUGAAUCUCAGGUUCCAUUGUCUACUUUUAAGUUGUAAUUUCUUCAGUCAUCAGUUUUCUUAUCUGUCAAGUAGAUUUAUCUACCUUAUAGGACUAUGGUUUUGAGGAUCCAAUGCAUAAAUGGACAAGGAUCGCCUCUGUCUUAUUCACUAGUAUCUGCAGAACACAGUGCAUUGCCCAACACAAUAAAUACUUGAUGAGUGAAGCAAGAAUAUUUGGAAAAUUAUAAAGCAGUCUACAAAUACAACUGCUGUUUUGAUCCAAAGGUAUUUUCCAAAUUUUGUCAUUUAUUCAUUUAUUCUUUCUUUUUUUAUCUUCUUGUUUCUGUGAUUUUUGAAUAACAAUGAGGAAAAUAAUAAUAAUAAUAAUAAUAAUAAUAAUAGCAAGUUACACUUAUUAGGCAUUAUUAUCUUCCAGGACUUACAAUAAGUUUGCUACAGGAAUUAUUUGAUUUAAUUUACAGGACAUCCCUAUGAGGUAGGUUCUAUUAUUAUCUCUGCUUUAUAGGUAGGUGAGGCACUUGAGGCUUAGAGAUGUUGAGUAAUAUUCUCAAGGUCGGCAAGCAAGUAGUUGGGUGGGGCUUCCACCCAGCUAGGCCUGAGCUCCUAUCGGACACACACACUGUUGCUAGCUGUAAUCUAUUGCCUAUUCUAUAUAAUCACUCAACCGGAAUUUAUUGUUAUUGCUCUUUUCUUUUUCCUUUUAUCUGGUGAAGAAAAGGUAAAAGUCCAAUCUGUUGGUGUAGAUGGCAGUCAACAAAAUUCAUUUUAUAGCCCCUAUGUUCUAGGAUUGUAUAAUGUGACUUUGUGUAUAUAUGUGUGUGUGUGUGUAUAGUUGUGCAUGAUAAAGUGAAGUGUGUAAACAGCAACUUCUGAAUUUGAGGAAUGUUUGUUUUAAGGAGAUAUAAUAAAUAUUUUAGAAAGGAGAUGGCUGGGCAUAUUUAGGAAAAGGUAUAGGGAAAAAAUGAACACCUAUGGCCAAGAGGUUUGGGAUCAUAUAUCAGCUCUGGUAGAAAUCAUUUAAAAACUGCAGAUUGGGGUGAAGGAAUACCACAGAAUGCCUCUUGAUGUUCAUUUUCCAAAUAUUAACUGUCAUGCAAAUAUUUUCAGAGCACACCAACAUCUGUGGUGGGUGUUAGACAUAUUUGUGUUGUGGAAAGAACUCAGAACUUGGCACCAAAGUGUCCAGUCUGCCACUUCUUAGCAGUGUGGCUUCAGAUUAAUUAGUGCCUUUCAGCCUGCUUCUCCUCUGUGAAAUAAUACUUACUAAGCACUUACUCUGGGACAUGAUUUACAUGUAUCUCAUUUAUUCUCACAAUAACUUGGUAUAUUUGGAUAAUUGGAAGGCAUUCGGUAAUAUUAUAAACAUUAUUUAGUGUUAUUAAUUACUGUUAUUAAUUCAUGUUAGUAUGGUGCUUGUCCAGGCUCCACAGCCUAGUGAGUAGUGAUGGGCAGAGGGACCCAUAGCUGAUCUCUGGGCCUCUUUAUUGAAGAACUGUCUGGAACAGUCCCUCCUGGGCCCAGAUUAGCUCUAAACCUGGACAUUUCCAGGAGUCAAGUUCUCAAAUAAUUUUUUAACUUAAUUCUUAAGCUAGUGCACACUUACCAUAUCCUAGGUACAAUGCUAAAAGCUUUACAUGAAUCCUUUAUUUUAGCCCUCCUAACAAUGUUAAUGAAAAGUAAUUUUUAUUGACCCCAUUUAGCAAAACAAAAAAGAAAAUCUAAGACUCAGAGAUAUUAUGUGACUUGACCAAGUUAUGUAGCAAGAAAGUGGCAGAUGAGGGAGGUUCUGUUCUCAGGUCUCUGACUCCAAAGUACAUACUCUUAUCUGAUAACUGCCCUUCUGCACUCUUUCUUCUCCUUCUCCCAGGCCCUAGUUCCUGGUUAUAGUUUGCUUCAGAGGUUAUCUGGAUUUCAGUUGCAUUCUUGAUCUCCAUGUUUGGUAGGUGUGGGCUGAGAUGGGUGAGUUUGAUGGACUCACAUUAUUGUGAAGUUCAUGGAACUCAUUUUGGCCCUCUUGUAGGCCAAUGAGGAGAGUCUGGGGGAAUCUAUAACUCCCUCAGAAAGAGCAGGGUGGGCUCAGGUAAAGUAUUGCCUUCAAAGCCCUUCCAGAAUAUCUCUUGGCUCAGAGUGCUUCAAUAAAUAGUUAAUCGGCUUAGUGCCUCCAAGCAGGCACUAACCUUCCCUUCGGGUCUUCUUUUUCAGUCUUAAGUGAUUACCUAAGGAAUUAAAUAUUCCUUUCCAAACACUGAUUAUUGUUAUUUAUUACUAUUAGCAUUUACAAAUAUG